AUGCAGCGCCCCACGCCUCCCGCCCGAGGGGGCCGCCUAAUUGGCUGCGGGACCGGAGGAAGGGAGGGCGGGCUGCGGGAGGGAGGAGAGGGGAGGGCGGCCGGCCCGCCUCACCCCGCCCCGCCCGCCGCCCCUGCGGGAGCCCGAGCGCCGGCGGCUCCACCCGCGUGCCGCGGACCGUCCCGGCGCCCGCGCCGCGCGCUCUCUCGCCCCGGAGGCUGCCUGUGGACGAGCUCCCCGAGGAGCCGCCGGGCCCCGGAAGUCGCAGGGCUGGGACACCCGACCCGGCAGGGAGCUGAGCCGCGGGGCCACGGCGCCCCGCUGCCUCCCCGAAGUCGGGCGGGCUCCCCGCGCGGCACAUGCAGCCCACUCCCAGCCGCCGCACGGCGCGCUCGCCCGACUUCGGCCGGCUCGCGGCGCUCGGGAAUGCGCGCUCUCCGCCGGGCCCUGCGCCGCGCCCGGGUCGGGGCUCCUGGCGGGGCCGCCCCGCGUCGCUGCGCACGUGCCCUGCUCUUGGGUCCAGCCGCCCGAUCCCCGCUAGCAGGACAGACGCCCGCUGCGCCCCACCCUGCCCGAGCGCGGACAGCCGGCGGGCGCACCCCGGCCCAGCCGGCCUGGAGUCUCCCCGGGGCCCUGGGGCUUCGCCCGCGGUGGGGCAGAAGGCGAAAGCAAAGCGCCGGACCCGGGCGGCUCUCCGCCGAGGAGCCCUGGCGCCGCUGGGCCUCUGACCUUCGCAGGCGCACACCGCCUUCCAUCCCAGAGCCCGGGGGGCAAUUGAUCUGAUUUUUUAAAUGCAUAAAUUAUACCUCGAUUAAAAAAUGAUAAUUAAAAAAAAGCACAUGAGACCUUUGCUGCUAA